GGGGCGCGGCCUCCUGUCUGCACCGGCAGCACCAUGUCGCUCACUGUCGUCAGCAUGGCGUGCGUUGGGUUCUUCUUGCUGCAGGGGGCCUGGCCACUCAUGGGUGGUCAGGACAAACCCUUCCUGUCUGCCCGGCCCAGCACUGUGGUGCCUCGAGGAGGACACGUGGCUCUUCAGUGUCACUAUCGUCGUGGGUUUAACAAUUUCAUGCUGUACAAAGAAGACAGAAGCCACGUUCCCAUCUUCCACGGCAGAAUAUUCCAGGAGAGCUUCAUCAUGGGCCCUGUGACCCCAGCACAUGCAGGGACCUACAGAUGUCGGGGUUCACGCCCACACUCCCUCACUGGGUGGUCGACACCCAGCAACCCCCUGGUGAUCAUGGUCACAGG